GUAAACCGGACCAGCCGCUGCGGGCAAAGGAAGGCUCUUGGCUCCUUCGGGAAACCCAGCCCCGUCACCGGGCUCCGAGCGGCUCGCAGGCGAGCGACAGCGGCCUCAGCCCCGGCAGCGCCCAGCGGCGGCUGCGGAAAGCGGAGGGAGUCCGACGCGGGCGCGGGCGGGGAGCGUGCGUCCGUUCGCACAGGCAGCGGGAGGAGGGGCGGCGCGAACCAUGGCCGGGGACAGCGAGCAGACCCUGCAGAACCACCAGCAGCCCAACGGCGGCGAGCCCUUCCUUAUAGGCGUCAGCGGGGGAACAGCUAGCGGCAAGAGGUAAAGUACAUUUAUGGAGAACAUCGGGGUGAAUGCCAAAGCGGCUUAUGUUCUAAAAUAGUGAAAAGAAUUGUGCAGUUGGAGUUAGACCUAUGGUUUGAGACUCAGCUUUGGGACUGAGCAAAUCAUUUCACGUGAUCAAUUUUCUAAGCUCCAGUUUCCUCAUUAGGAAAAAAGAAGACAAAGUAAUACUUGUUGUAAUGGAAUUAAAUGAGAUAAUGUCUUCAGAAUGCCAUUCUUCCGUGUGUGCUAAGAUCGUGCAGCUCCUGGGGCAGAAUGAGGUGGACUAUCGCCAGAAGCAGGUGGUCAUCCUGAGCCAGGAUAGCUUCUACCGUGUCCUUACCUCGGAGCAGAAGGCCAAAGCCCUGAAGGGCCAGUUCAACUUUGACCACCCGGAUGCCUUUGACAAUGAACUCAUUCUCAAAACACUCAAAGAAAUCACUGAAGGGAAAACAGUCCAGAUCCCCGUGUAUGACUUUGUCUCCCAUUCCCGGAAGGAGGAGACAGUUACUGUCUAUCCCGCAGACGUGGUGCUCUUUGAAGGGAUCCUGGCCUUCUACUCCCAGGAGGUACGAGACCUGUUCCAGAUGAAGCUUUUUGUGGAUACAGAUGCGGACACCCGGCUCUCACGCAGAGUAUUAAGGGACAUCAGCGAGAGAGGCAGGGAUCUUGAGCAGAUUUUAUCUCAGUACAUUACGUUCGUCAAGCCUGCCUUUGAGGAAUUCUGCUUGCCAACAAAGAAGUAUGCUGAUGUGAUCAUCCCUAGAGGUGCAGAUAAUCUGGUGGCCAUCAACCUCAUCGUGCAGCACAUCCAGGACAUCCUGAAUGGAGGGCCCUCCAAACGGCAGACCAAUGGCUGUCUCAACGGCUACACCCCUUCACGCAAGAGGCAGGCAUCGGAGUCCAGCAGCAGGCCGCAUUGACCCGUCUCCAUCGGACCCCAGCCCCUAUCUCCAAGAGACAGAGGAGGGGUCAGGAGGCACUGCUCAUCUGUACAUACUGUUUCCUAUGACAUUACUGUAUUUAAGAAAACACCAUGGAGAUGAAAUGCCUUUGAUUUUUUUUUUCUUUUUGUACUUUGGAACGACAAAAUGAAACAGAACUUGACCCUGAGCUUAAAUAACAAAACUGUGCCAACUACUACUGGUGAUGCCUAAUUAUGAAUCCAACGUGUAACCAGUUAUAAAUACAUAUAUAUAUAAAAAAGGAUCUAUUUUUGUGUAAAUGUACAAAUACUGUAAAGCUGUUUGCCAUAAGUAUUUUGCAGGAGGGUCUGUACUUGAGUGUUUUAGGACUGGAGCUGGAAUUUCACCAAGGGGAAAUUGCCUGUUGUGUCCCAGGGUGGGGAGGCUCGGGCAUCUGUGAGAGACAGGGAGGGUGGCUAAGGUCCAGUUGCUUUUGAGUGCCCCGUGGAACUUGAUGGGAAUGGGGUUGGAAAACCUUGAUUGCCUCCUCUGUCACAUGCCACUCUUGGAGCUGGAGCUUAGUGAUAUGUCAAUGAGAGAUACUCUUGUCUUUUUUUUUUUUCUUUUCUUUUUUUUUUUUGAGUUGAAAUUAGGUAAAAUCUCAACUCAAAAAUCAAACUCAGGGAAGAGGCCCACUGAGGAGAACAAGUCUUCUGCAUUUUCUUCCUGCCCUGCUCCCACCUUCUCGCCUCUGGCUGCUUGGAUAGCUUGGUGACUCCUUCCUCACCCUCCUGCUUCUCUGUCUCUCCAAGAAGCCAGAGCUGCCUCUUUCCUUCCCUGGAAGAGAUUUUAUGGGAUCGCUUCCUGAUAGAAGAUGGGAAGGAGAGGGCAGAACUUUGCCUGCUGUCAUAUCUGAAGAAUCACUGGUUCUUUCUGCAUCCCAGGGGCGUAACUGAUCUGACUCCUUGGGCUUUUUCCUGUAUUGUGGAAUAUAGAGUGGACCAUUGCAGGCUGGGUGUGGGUGAGGGCUUCGGUAACUGAUGCCGGCAGCAGCGCCUCAUGGAGUGGCAGGGGAGCUCUGUCUGUGGAGGGGUAGUAGUUUCCGCUUCCUGGAGGUUUGCAGUGAGGUGAGGAGAGUAACUUUGGUCAGGGAUUCUCACUAGCAGCGUCAUGGCCAGGAUGCUUUACUUAUUUGCAAUACCACCUAGUGGAUAUGGCAACUGCAGAGCAUAAAAGGGGCUCGGAAAAGCAGUUUUUACAAAGUAUUUAAAAGGAGAGUAUUUAAAUCAUAGGUACCUAAGUUGGAGCCUGAGGUUGAAAUAUUUGGGGUGGAGAUUUCUAGCUUUCCUGAGAGCUGCUGCUUGGUGGUAGUGUUUUCUCUGGAAGUACAGAUUCCUGACAUUCUGGGUGGAGGGGAGCCCAAGUGAGCCUGAAGGAGUUCUGAUUAUAGAGUCCCGAGCCUCAGUUUCUGACUGCAGAAGAGCCAGAGAUGUUCAUUUCAUUGUUGACCACCCUAGUGCUUGGUGGACUGUGCCCUUAGCUAUCCCACUGUGGCUGCCAUUGCCAGAAACAUUUUGGAGAACCUUUUCUUCCCAUUGCUCUCAGAGCCUGUUCGAGCCAUUCAGGUAAAUUGGUCUCCAUUAUUACCUGGUCACACCAGAUUUUCCCCCAGACUCAGCACCAUCCAGUCUGAUUCCCCGUUUCUGGGCUCAGUUUGACUCUAAAUCUGUUUUGCUAUUUUAAAAAGUCAAACCUGGUCCCCAGCAGAGCUUGCCACCCGGAGACUUUCAGGAGACCGUGCAGGCUCUGAAGGGAGCUCCCAGUCACAGCAGCCGCCUACUUGGAGCAAGGGAAGGCUCCCAAGAUGCCUCCUUUGAAAGCCGGUGCUCACCAAGAUCAGUUCAGGAUCAAUCAUUAUCCUUGUAGUCAUGCCUUGAUCAGUUCUGAGAUGAAGCAGGGAAUGCAGGCCUGGGUUAGUAUCCUGAGGACACAGGGCCCCUGGCCUUGAUGGCACUGGGCUGUGCUCAGGUGAAGCCCACCCGUGUCUGGGAGAGCCUUGGCUUUUCAGUGGGCAGCAUGCUCAACUUUACUUGAAGCUCCCAGGUGCCAAACCAUUUAGUGCCUUGGCUGUUUAUCCCACUGCCUUGGAAGAUGGACUCCUCUCAUCUCUGAGCCUUUACCUAGCUGCUUCCUCAUCUACCUGUGGUGUUGGGACCAAGCCUCCAAUAUCUCUGAAUAGCCCACUCCUAGCUUGGAAACAGCUAUAAGGGCUGCCCUGCCCCUUGUCAAAUGAUCACCAAUUCUUGGUGGCUUGGCUGGGGACAAUGAACAGUGUCUGCUGGGGUCUGUGACACACUGUUUCUGGAACAAGGAAGGGAUGGAAGGCUCUACCCCUCCGUGGCAGCCCAGCAUUUGGCCAACUCUGUAUCUGAACUUGAGCUUUCUAUGGAACAAACAAUGGUCUUAGUUUUUUAAGAGCCUCUGGGUCUCUGAUUCCAUGGAGAGUCAGGAGUAGAAUUAGUGGACCAGAAACCAUGACAUUUGCCAUCUAGGUACUCUGCUGUUCAGGGUGGAGGCACAGAUGAGCAGAGUGGGGUGAUGUUGGUUGUAUGUGCAUAGAAGUCCCCUGGCUCCAGAGCCAUCCAGUGGUGCUUGGUUCUCUCUUCCUGCCCAGGUAUUGUGUGUGGACCAAGUGUUUAGGAAACAAGCAUAGAAGCAUUAUGUCACAGGAAGGCCUGGCCUCUCACUCCUUCACACUAAUGAGCCUUCUACUGACCCAAGUUUCUUUUUCUCGGGCAGCCUGGGACCACUAUGAGCAGAGAGAUGGGAGUCUGUGUAAGAAGGAUGCAAGUAUCCUUUGAUUUGGAGUGGACAGAGCAGGUCCUUGCAAAGGCAGUGGGUUAAACAACGGGAUGUCUGUGGGACAGGCCAGGGAAGGAGGGCAGAGACAGGGUCUCCAGUUCACCUUGCCGCAGAACUAGCCUAAUCAUCCCUGCUUCUGGUCUUGGCCACUUGGCAAUCAUGGGGAAGUUGACUCCCCGCCUCACUUGGGCUUGGAGCUGGAUACUUGUGGCCACGCCCAGGAUAGGUUGCCAGAGUUUCAUUAGGCCGCUGGGUCGGGCUGGAGGCUUGUGUACACCUCGGAGCAGUCGGGCAGCAGGAGGGCCGGAAGCCUGGUUGGUUUGUAUAUGACCUCUCUUGCCCUUGUGCACUUUCCUUGAUUUAGCAACCUUGACCUGCACUGGCCCUCACAGCUGUUGGAGGGAAGUAGCCUCUUGCAGGGAAAUAUUUUCCCCUGCCCUGGAAUCUCCUAUGUGCCUGUUAAAGAUUCCAGGGCCAAGAACUCGGCAGGCUGAGGAGCAGCUAGGUAGGUGGGUUAUGCGGUUCAGGACUGCUUCUGGAAGGGACUGCCUGUACUUCUGUACCACCGUUGCCCUUUACACUUUGCUCAGGGCGGGGUGGGGGAAGCAUUCAAACAAAACAAGGAAGGGAACUGUCUGGCAAAGCAUAAGUGGAUGCAUCCAGAGCUCAGUCCCCUUUAAUCUUUUGUCUCUGGGCGUUCUGCUGCCUUCCUCAUACCGGGGACUGGCAUUCCAGGUCAGCUUGGCUGUGGUCUUAGAGGCAGGGAGUGCCUACCCAGUCCUGCCUCAGGAGCAGGGUGAGUAGCUAAAUACAGACUUAGGCUUUUUUUUCCCCCCUUUUAAGAUGCUUGCUCCUCUCCCUUUUCUUUUUACCACCCUACCUUUAUUGUUAGUGGUUACAAAGUGACCACAUAUUAUGUACUUUGCUGUAAAUAAAGACAGACAAAAAGGC